AGAUUCUUCCUGUUCUCCCUGAGCAGCAUUGUGUCCUCCAGGGUAUGGGUCAGGACCUCUUCUGAAAUGGGAGUUUAAGACCUACAAUCAGACAAGGGCAGGGAGCUGUCUUGACCCCCAGUGGAGGCUGACAAUUUUUUUCCUGUGUACACUGGACCCCUUUCAUAGAGGUGGGUGCUAUGCAAGUGGAGCUGGUGACUGAUGGCUGACCAUUGAUACAGGCUAGGAAUACCAAUGAGCAAGGACUGAUCUUAAAGGAGCCAAGUGGUGGUGCCAGUGAAAGCUUGAAACAGAAUCCUACCCAAUGGCCUCUCUCCUGUUCUAUCCAUAUGACAUGGAGACAAAUGCUGUGGAGGAGAGGGGACUCAGAGUCAGAGACUUGGUCCGAGAGGAGCAGACAUCAUUGGCAGAGGACGGAGCUCCAGGCUCUGCAAGGAAUCAAGGUCAGAAACCUGAGGGAGGACUGAGGCACCCCCAUGACCCUCGACCACAUCUGCACCCCUCGCCACUACUUUUCCCCCUGCCCCACCCCGCCCCGCCCCGCCUCGCCUCGCCCCGCCCCGCCUCGCCUCGCCCCGCCCCCACACGGGCAGAAUCGGGUUCGCUCCUGCUGUAAAUCCAGGGAAGCUCCAGGCGUGGGGGCCGGAUGUGACCUCCAUUGGCUUCCGCCUCUGGGAUCUGAGAGAAGCGAAAGCGUCUUUCUGAGGGGUGUCUUGAGAGUGGCAGAGGGCAGCGGGUCCAGGCUCCAUGAGGAGGCAAGCCUUGGGAAUCUGAGGGAUGGAGACUCAGUUCCGCAGAGGGGGUCUGGGGUGCAGCCCUGCCAGCAUCAAGAGGAAGAAGAAGAGGGAGGACUCAGGAGACUUUGGACUCCAGGUGAGCACUAUGUUCUCAGAGGACGACUUCCAGUCAACAGAAAGAGCCCCAUAUGGUCCACAACUACAGUGGUCCCAGGAUCUGCCAAGAGUCCAGGUUUUUAGAGAACAGGCCAACCUGGAGGACAGGAGUCCCAGGAGAACCCAGAGGAUCACUGGAGGAGAACAAGUGCUGUGGGGCCCCAUCACCCAGAUAUUUCCCACAGUUCGGCCUGCUGACCUAACCAGAGUCAUCAUGCCUCUUGAGCAAAGAAGUCAGCACUGCAAGCCUGAGGAAGGCCUUCAGGCCCAAGAAGAAGACCUGGGCCUGGUGGGUGCACAGGCUCUCCAAGCUGAGGAGCAGGAGGCUGCCUUCUUCUCCUCUACUCUGAAUGUGGGCACUCUAGAGGAGUUGCCUGCUGCUGAGUCACCAAGUCCUCCCCAGAGUCCUCAGGAAGAGUCCUUCUCUCCCACUGCCAUGGAUGCCAUCUUUGGGAGCCUAUCUGAUGAGGGCUCUGGCAGCCAAGAAAAGGAGGGGCCAAGUACCUCGCCUGACCUGAUAGACCCUGAGUCCUUUUCCCAAGAUAUACUACAUGACAAGAUAAUUGAUUUGGUUCAUUUAUUGCUCCGCAAGUAUCGAGUCAAGGGGCUGAUCACAAAGGCAGAAAUGCUGGGGAGUGUCAUCAAAAAUUAUGAGGACUACUUUCCUGAGAUAUUUAGGGAAGCCUCUGUAUGCAUGCAACUGCUCUUUGGCAUUGAUGUGAAGGAAGUGGACCCCACUAGCCACUCCUAUGUCCUUGUCACCUCCCUCAACCUCUCUUAUGAUGGCAUACAGUGUAAUGAGCAGAGCAUGCCCAAGUCUGGCCUCCUGAUAAUAGUCCUGGGUGUAAUCUUCAUGGAGGGGAACUGCAUCCCUGAAGAGGUUAUGUGGGAAGUCCUGAGCAUUAUGGGGGUGUAUGCUGGAAGGGAGCACUUCCUCUUUGGGGAGCCCAAGAGGCUCCUUACCCAAAAUUGGGUGCAGGAAAAGUACCUGGUGUACCGGCAGGUGCCCGGCACUGAUCCUGCAUGCUAUGAGUUCCUGUGGGGUCCAAGGGCCCACGCUGAGACCAGCAAGAUGAAAGUUCUUGAGUACAUAGCCAAUGCCAAUGGGAGGGAUCCCACUUCUUACCCAUCCCUGUAUGAAGAUGCUUUGAGAGAGGAGGGAGAGGGAGUCUGAGCAUGAGAUGCAACCAGGGCCAGCGGGCAGGGAAAUGGGCCAAUGCAUGCUUCAGGGCCACACCCAGCAGUUUCCCUGUCCUGUGUGAAAUCAGGCCCAUUCUUCCCUCUGUGUUUGAUGAGAGAAGUCAGUGUUCUCAGUAGUAGAAGGCACAGUGAAUGGAAGGGAACACAUUGUAUACUGCCUUUAGGUUUCUCUUCCAUCGGGUGACUUGGAGAUUUCUUUUUGUUUCCCUUUGGUAAUUUUCAAAUAUUGUUCCUGUAAUAAAAGUUUUAGUUAGCUUCAACAUCUAAGUGUAUGGAUGAUACUGACCACACAUGUUGUUUUGCUUAUCCAUUUCAAGUGCAAGUGUUUGCCAUUUUGUAAAACAUUUUGGGAAAUCUUCCAUCUUGCUGUGAUUUGCAAUAGGUAUUUUCUUGGAGAAUGUAAGAACUUAACAAUAAAGCUGAACUGGUGUUGUGAAACAGAGAAAUAAAAGGAGAAGGUCAUUAA